AUUCCAGUUUGGAAUUAUAAAGAUGCUAUGAACAUUCUUUUUCUUCAACAUCUGUUUUGUGGACAUCUAGUUUGAUUCCUGUUGGAUAAAUACUUAUGCAAAACUGUACAAUCUAAAGUGGACUGCAUUUUGCCCCCUCGGGUGAAUUGUUUAUAAGCUACCUAGAUACUUACCUGUAUCUCAUCAAUAAUAAAAUCACAAUCUGAGGUAAUUACAUGUUUUUGAAUCUUAACUGGCUCUUACUGAAAGACUGCUUAAACGAACAAUUAAAUUGGAUAUUUAUUUUUCUAUUCUAAUAACUCUGAGAAUUUGUUUAGAGAAAAGUUUUUGAAGAUGUUUAAUGGGUUAGUUUUGUUGAGAUAGUGUGUUUUUCAUGUUUUGGUUGGCAGCCUGUAGGAAUUAAGCCAUAAUAAUAGUUUAAGUUUAGAUUCUACUUAAUAGAAUUGUAAAAAUUUGUUUUCAAAAACAGCUUUUAAGAUGCUUAGUGGAUUAGUUUUUGUGGGGUUGCCAGCUUUCAAGAUUUAAAGCCACAAUAAUAGUUUAAAUUUAGAUUGUGUUAGUAUAGUAGUAGUUUCAUAGGUCUUCUUUUAAACGUGUGAGGGAAGGAGCAUUGCAGCUACUGGGACAUCUGGAAUACUGCUGAUUUCUUUCAUAAAAUCUCUACCAAAAGGAUAGCCUCUAGGCUUUAGAACACACGAAGGCUCUAUACUGUUAGAUUCCCCAAAUUGUCAGUAUAGUUAGUUCUCUUUCCCCACUUGUGACUUGGGAAGUUCUCUUAUCCAAGUUUGGGUCUUGCUUAUAAGCUAACCUGACUAUGUUGUUGUUGGUGGUGGUGGUGGUCUGUUACAGUGUCUGGUGCUGAAAUAGUAUGAUGUCUUAUUAGCUUAUAUUAUUAUUAGCUUAUUAUUCUAUAGGUAGCUGAAUACAUAGGAAUAGUUUAUAGGAGAAGAGGAAAUUUAAUCAGUUCUCUUACACUUUUCUAACCUAAUAGCUAGCUAAAAGAGGACUUUGUGGAGGUGUUUUUCUUUUUCCUUUCAUUUACUCUUCUUUUUGUUGUGUGUGUGUGUGUGUGUGUGUGUGUGUGUGUGUGUGUGUGUGUAGUUUUUUGGUUUUCGAGUUUUUUUUUUUGUCUUAUAAUAAUCCUCUGAAGUAGGUAAUCUUGUUACCUCCCUUUUACAAAUGAAGACACCAAUGCUCUUGCAUUUCAUUCAAAAAAUUAUUAAAAUUAUUGGACAUCUUCUGUCUGCCAGUUUUACUCAUAAGGAAUACAAAACAGAAAAGACAUAUUCCAUGCCCUUAAGAAAUUUAGUCUGUUAUAGAGAGAUAUAUUCAAGACUACUCUUAAGACCUAGAAAAGUGGUGACUGGGAGUGGAGGGAGUAAUACAUUGCCACCAACCCCCAGAGCAUUUCCUCUGUCUUCCAACUCUUAAGAGUCUCAUUGUUAAUGUGUCAUUCUGUAAUUAUUUCAUGUUUAUCAUAUACUAGACCCUGUUCUUGGUACGAGAGUACAGUGGUAAGCAAGACAGACACAGUUCUUGUCUAUAUAUGGCCACCCACUCUCUUUGCAAUACUUGAGAUAACUUUGGAGGAUCACUCACUUUUUUCUCUUCAUUAAGAAGAGGUAGAAGACUGGUAUAAAUUAUAAAAUAUGACACUUAUAAAAUACUAAAUAAGAACAAAGUUCUUUUUAAAGUCUUUUAAGAGUUCAGAAAUGUUUACAUUUUAGUCUAAGUUUUAGAAUAUAUGUAAAUUUUUACUCAGUAAUUAAAAAAUAUUGUGUUAGGUCCUGGACAUACAGUGAUGAACAAGAUACUAAGAUCUCUCCUCUCAUGAUCCUUUUAUUUUAUUGGGUGAGGUAGACAUUAAACAAGUGACUAAAUAAUUAAGCAUUACAAUUCAGAUAACGAUAAAUGAUACUCCACAAUUUUUAAAAGGGAAAGGGAGGCAAGUGAUGGUGGGUAGGGUAACCUUAGAUAGGGUGGCCAGGAAAAGCUUCUCUGAGAAUCUUCUCUGAGGAGAUGACAUUUGAGUGCCGACCUGAGUAAUAAGAAGCCAGCUUGAGUCAUGAUCUCCUGGUGACACACAUGAGGUAGAAGGAACAGUAGGUACAAAAAAUCUGAAGCUGGGAAUGAGUUUGCGGUAUUUGAAGAAUACAGGAUCCCAGUAUGCUGGAACUUACGGAAGGAAGUAGAGAAUGAUAGAAAAGUUCAAGCAGGAAGUAGUUCAUGUAUUACAUAUUUAGUCAUGGCAAGUAGUAUCCUAAGUGCAUGAAAGCUGAUGAGAGGAUUUUAUGCAGAGAAUAGUGCAAUCUGUUUUUUUUUUUUUAAUACCCUGGCUGUUGUUGGAACAGUGGAUUGUAGGGGGAUAUGAGUAAAAGCAGGAAAAUUAGUUAGGCUAUUGCAGAAGUUCAGUAGAUAAUUCAAGGCUCUUGCUCAGAUGAUGGCAAUGGAAGAUUUUUUUUUGUAAGUAGAUGGAUUUAAGGCAUUUUUGGAUAUAAAACUAGUAGGCCUUGCUUGCUGAUAGAUUCAAUGUGGAGGGGAAACAGAGGAAUCAAGGAUGAUUCCUUUCAGUCUAAAGCAGUUCUUCUAGUAUUUAUUAUACCACAGGUUUGUGUGUAAUGAAUUUUCUCAGUCUGUGUUUAUCUAUGAAUGUCUUUAUUUUGCCUUCUGCUUUAAAAGAUGGUUUUGCUGGAAAUAGAAUGUCUGGUUUACAGUUUUGUUUGCUUGUUUUUUCUUUCAUUGUUUUGAAUAUGUUAAUCCAUUACAUUUUGGACAUCAGCCAUUAAUUAUAUUAAUGUCUGCCUGUACGUAAGUUUUCUUUUGUUGGUAUUAAGAUUUAUCCUAGAUUGAUUCUGUCACUCAUUCACUUCUCCUGUCUCUCUGACUUUUAACAGUUUGACUACGUAUAUAGUGGAUCACUUCAUGUUUGUCCUACUUGGGCUUUGUUGAGCUCACAUAGAUUAGUUAGGUUUGGGAUGUUUUCAGCCAUUAUCUUUCCAAAUACUUUUUCAGUCCCUUGAUUCUCUCCUCCCCUUCUAAAAUGCCCAUUUCACGUAUGUUGAAAUGAUUGAUGUUAUUAUUCUCUUCUCUCUGAAGCUCUAUUUACUUUUUUCUCUGAUUAUCUUUAUUUGUGCUCUAGUUUCUCUAUUAAGAUUUCCUGUUGUCUGAUUCUUUGUCAUUGUGUUUUUCUUUGCGUGUUUAAACACAGGCUGCCUCAUCCUAGCAACACUACUAUUUUAACCAUGUGGGAUAGGUCAUGGCAGCAGCCAUAAGCAAGAAUAAUAGACUCUCAUAGUUACUACUACCUAAAGUUCAGUAGUCACUAAUGACUAAACACUUCCCAAUAUGUUGUUUGCCUGUAGUUAGUUUCCAGAGCCUAGUUUCUGACCAUUUUGUGUCAUUUUAUACUUGUUUGUAGGGAGGAUUGGCCAGCCUCUUUACUUCCUUUUCCAGAUAUCUCAAUCUUCUCAUAAAGAUUUUAUUAGGUUUUCUUCUAGAAGUUUUAUAGUUGUAGUGUUUUUCUUUUAGAUGUUUGAACCAUUUUGUGUUAAAUUUGUGUUUGCUUUAAGUUGAACUUCAAGGUUUAUUUUUUACAAUAUGGAUGGAUAUCCAGUUGUCCAGUACCAUUUAUUGAAAAGUCUGCCUCUCCCCAGUCACUUCCUAUAUCAAAAAUCAUUAUAUGUGGGUGUUUUUCUAGGCUCUUAUUUUCCAUUGAUUGCUGUGUCUGCCUUUAUGACAUCACUACACUGUCUUGUUUACUGUGCUUUAUAGAAAGUCUUGAUAUCAGAUAUAUAAAUGGUUCAUAUAUUUUUUGGCAUUUCCAUACAAAUUUCAGAGUUACUUUGUCAAUUUUUAUUUUUAAAAAAAGUUCUACUUGGAUUUUUAUUGGGAUUACAUCAAAUUUAUAGAUCAAUUUGGACACAAUUGAUGUCUUAUUAACAAAUUUUAAUUCAUGAGCUUGGUGUAUCUCCAUUUCAGUUGGUUCUUCUAUAAUAUCUUUCAGCGUGUUUUGUUAUUUUCUGUGUAUAGGUUUUGUACACAUUUUAUUAAAACUAAAAGUUUUUAGAUGCUACUGAGUAUGGCAUUUAAAAAUUUUUGUUAUCCAUUGUUUUAUUGCUAAUAGUUAUAGUGAUCUUGUAACCUGCAAACUUGCUACAUUCACCUAUUAAAUCUAGUAGCUUUUAUGUAGUCUUUAGGAUUUUCUACCCACUCAAUCAUAUUAUCUACGAAUAAAAAGAGUUUUAAUUUCUUGUUAAUUUAUAUGCCAAUUUCUUUUUCUCACCUUAUUGUACUGCUAGGACCUCUGGGAGAUAGGCUAAUAGAAAUGUGAGAGUGAAUUUCCUUGCCUUGUUCCGGAUCUUAAGGAAAAAACAGUGAUUCAUUCACCAUACAAUAUGAAGUUAACAUUAGCUUGUUCAUGGACGCUCUUCAUCAGGUUAAACAUGUUACUUUCUGUUUCUAUUUUGCUAAGAGUUUUUUUUUUAAAAUCAUAGUUACUUGCUGAUUUUUUUAUUUUUCUUAGACGGAGUCUGGCUCUAUCAACCAGGCUUUAGUGCAGUGGUGCAAUCUCGGCUCACUGCAACUUCUGUCUCCCAGGUUCAAGCGAUUCUCCUUCCUCAGCCUCCCGAGUAGCUGGGACUACAGGCAUGCACCGCCGUGUCCAACUAAUUUUUGUAUUUUUAGUAGAGACAGGGUUUCACCAUGUUGUCCAGGAUGGUCUCGAUCUCUUGACCUCAUGGUCUGCCUACCUUCGCCUCCCAAAGUGCUUUGAGAUGGGAUUACAGGUAUGAGCAACCGUGCCCAGCCACAUGCUGAUUUUUAUCCAACAAUUUUUCUAUACUUACUAAUAGUUUGUUUCUCUAUUAUCACUUUUCUUAUUCUUUUCCCCUGAACUAUCUAAUCUGCUAUAAAUCCCAUCUAAUAAAUUUUCUCUUCUAGAUCUUAUAUUUUUUUCAGUUCUAGAAAUUCAACUUUUUGGGUUUUUUUUGAGACAGAGUUUCACUUUUGUUGCCCAGGCUGGAGUGCAGUGGCACAAUCUCAGCUCACUGCAACCUCCGCCUCUUGAAUUCAAGUGAUUCUCCUGCCUCAGCCUCCCAAGUAGCUGGGAUUAUAGGCGCUCACCACCAUACCCGGCUUAUUUUUGUAUUUUUAGUAGAGACGGGGUUUCACCAUGUUGGCCAGACUGGUCUCGGACUCGUGACCUCAGGUGAUGCACCCACCUCAGCCUCCCAAAGUGCUGGGAUUACAGGUGUGAGCGAAAUUCCACUUUUUUAUAGAAGUUUUUAUAUCCUCCAUUUUGUUUCUGUCUUAAAUACCUGUCCUAAAUUCCUUGACUGCUAAUUGUAGUAUCUCUAUCAUUUGUUUAUCAUUUUCUCUAUCAUCUUAUCAUUUUGUUUCUGUCUUAAAUACCUGUCUUAAAUUCCUUGAUUGCUAAUUGUAUUAUCUCUAUCAUUUUUGUGGUCCCUUUUUUUUGAGAUGGAGUUUCACUCUUGUUGUCCGGGCUGCAAUGCAUUUCAGAACCACAGCUCACUGCAACCUCUGCUGCCUGGGUUCAAGCGAUUCUCCUGCCUCAACCUCCGGAGUAGCCUCCAGAGUAGCUGGGAUUACAGGUAUCCGCCACUACACCCAGCUAAUUUUUUGUAGUUUUAGUAGAGACAGGGUUUCACCAUGUUGGCCAGGCUGGUCUCGAACUCCUGACCUCAUCUGAUCCACUUGCCGUGGCUUCCCAAACUGUUGGGAUUACAGGCGUAAGCCACUGUGUCCGGCCUGUGGUCCAUUUUAUUUACUGAUUUUCGUUGCAAUUACAGGUCAUAAUUUUCUGCUUCUUUGCAUAUGUAAUACUUUUUAAUUUAGUGCUGAACACUGAUUUUUAUGGUUUUUGAGCAUUUGAGUUUUCUUCUCUUCCUUUGAAGUGUAUUGAAGUUUGUUCUUCUCUUCCUUUAAAGUGUAUUGAAGUUUGUUUCAGCAGAACUGGAACAUGUGUCAGCCACUUGUAGAUCCCUGGUAGCUCUUUGCCCAGCCUUUUGGAGUUUUUAUCUACAUAUAUACAGUUUAGUUUUCAGCUAUAGAUUCCAAAUUCCAAAUCUACAUAGGGAUUUGUGUAAAUUUUGAAGCUGUUUAUUUUUCUUCCAUAUGAUUCUUUGCCACCUCGAACACUAACCUCCUUCUCUUUAGCUCUGCAGUACUGCCUUGCUUUGCUUAAGUUGCUUCUUUCUGCACGACAGUCAAGUUGUCUUCAGAUAGAAUCGUCUCAUUUGUUUUUUUCUUUUUCAGGUCUAACAGUCUAUGCUUUUUGUUGUCCAAUUUCUGAAAACACUUGUUUCUGAUAUUUUGUUCAUGUUUUGAGAUGGUGGUGCUGGGAGAGUUGCUGCAGUAUCAGGUACUCCACUGCGGCCACAUGCAGAAGUCUAUUAACAGCUAUUUUAAGGAUUCAAUAAAAUAUAUAGGCCCCUUCACACCCUCUUUUUCUUUAGUGAUUUAUUUUCCACUAUUCUCCACUAAACCUGUUUCAGACUUCUUUAGCUCAAGCUACUAAACUCGCCUCUUCUUUUCUUGCUGCCGGUAAAUGAUCUUGCCUUCUACUUCUCUGAGAAAAUAGGAAGUUGCCUUGUGGUACUCCACCAAAUUAAUACAUUUCUUGUCCCUAACUUAAUACUUGCUCAAUUCUAUACCUGUUCUUGUCUUCUUUCCCUUAUCUCUCAACAGAAGAGUUGUCCUUCUGCCUGUCUGAAUGCUGAUCUCUCUCUGCCUACCCUCUAGGUCUCAUCCAUUCCUAUCUCAGAAUUCAUGUUAUGAUUCAUUCUCUUUCUCCUACUUCUUUAUUUUCUUAUUUUUUACUAGCCUAUUCUCAUGAAUAGUUAAAUGCUUAAUUUUACCCCCAUAUUUAAAAAAGAAAUCCUUCCUGAAACCCACAACCUUUCCUCUAGCUACCACUGUAUCUUCUUCCCUUUGAAAGAAGAAAGUCAAAGUUUAGUCAAAGUGUUGAUUGAAUUAGUCUCAUGCCUCACCUUCCAUUCAGUUUUGAACCCCAGUAACAAAAAUCUUUAAUACCACUCCUCUGAAACUUUUAUAAAGGAUACCAUGACCCCUCACUGCUGAAUAUAAUAGGUAAUAUCACUUCCAAAUGACAGCCUUUUUUCAGUUCACUCUGUUGACCAUUUCCAUACACACACUACCCCCUCAUCCCCCCAGUUUGGUACAUUCUCAUUUUUAAAAUUCCUUAAGAUGUCACACUAUCCUGGUUUUCCUGUUACAUUUUAGGCCGUUCCUUCUCACACCCUUCAAGGGUGUCUGUUGCUUUGCAUUUUGUCUAUAUUUGUCCAAAAUAAUCUCAUCUACUUUGAUGGUUUCAAUUAGUCUCAUUAUACCAAUGACUCCUAAUUAUAUGUCCCCAUCCUAAGCUCUAGGCCCAUAUAAUCCAACUCUUUAUCAGCUGAUCAGUUUUACCUGGAUGUCACAUAAGUACUUCAAACUCAACUUUUCCAGAGCCAAACUUGUAUCAUACCCCCACUUCUAUAACUAUCUGUAUUAGUCUCCUAUUGCUGCUAUAACAAAUUAACAUACAUUUAGAGGCUGCAUAAAAUAACACAAAUUGAUUAUUUUAGACUUCUGUGUGCCAGCAGUCUGACAUGGGUUUCACGGGGAUAAAACUAAGUUGUUAGCAGUGCCAUGGGUUUUUUGUUUUGUUUUGUUUUGUUUUUUUUCUGGAGACCCUAGGGAAGAAUAUGUUUCCUUGCCUUUUUUAGCUUCCAGUAGCUGCAUCUUCAAAGCCAUUAAUGGCUGCUUGAGCCUUUUUACAUUGCAUCAUUCUGACAGGGCUCUUUUUUGUAGUCAAAUCUCUUUCAGCCUCGCUUUUAUCAGGAUACCUGAGUAUACAUUGAUCCUACUCAGGGAAGCCAAGAUAAUCUCCCCAUCUUAAGGUCCUUGAUUUGGUCCCAUGCCAUGCAAAUUUCCAGGGGUUCAAAGAUUAAGACAUGAACAUUUCUGGGGUCAUUAUCCUAUCAUACUAUCUUAGUGAAUGGUACUCACUCAUGUAACCUAAAAACCUAGAGGUCAGUCUUGACUCUUCCUCAGCCUGCUUUACAACUAGUCAGUCACCAGAUCCUAUCAGUUCUGACUCCUUGGUUGCUCUAUUUUUGUGUAUUCCUACUGCUACUGCAUUAAUCCAGAUCAUAAUUAUUUGAGAUACUGCAACUCUUUUUCUGCUUCUAGUCUUUCCACAUUCGUUCUCCACACUAUCAUCAUAGUCGUCUUUAUAAAGUUCUGUUUAUUUCACACCUUUGCUUAAAACCUUUCAUUGGCUCCCCAUUGUUCUGCCUUAUGGUGUGGAAGAUUCUUCAUACUCAGACCUUACCUUUUUUGUCCAACCUCAUCUUUCUCCACUCUCCCCACAGCCUAUCAGCAAACUGUGGAAUAGAAGACAAUAUUUACUCCCUCAAUCUGUAAGAGCAUUAUCCAUGGAACUUUCUGUGGUGGUAGAAAUGUUUUAUAUCAUAUAUGCACUAUUCAAUAUGGUAAUCAGUAGCCAUGUGUGGCUACCGAAUACUUGAAAUGUGGUUAGUGUGACUGAGGAAUUGAACUUUUAAUUUUGUUUAAUUUUAAUGAAUUUGAAGUUAAAUAGCCACAUGUGGCUAGUGGUAAUGAUUUAGACAACAGAGAUCUCGAACAGUGCUUCUCAACCAGAGGCAAUAUUUGCCCUCCACGCCCCUAGGGGACAUUUGACAAUAUAUGGAGACAUUUUGGGUUUUCACACUUGGUGAGUUCUACUGGUAUCAGAUGGGAAGAGGCCAAGGAUGCUGUUUCAGCAUCCUCCAAAACAGGAUGUCCCCCGCCCCCAUAACAGACUUAGCCCAAAAGGUCAGAGUGCUGAGGUUAAGAAACUCUAUUCUAGACUGUUCCUUCUUUGUUCGUAACACGUACUUAUAGUUUAGGAUUCGUCUUAGAUAUCAACCCCUCUGGAAAGCCUUCUAUGAUUUCUCAGGUCUGAAUUUUAUAUUUUCUGUUCCAUUAUAUCCUUACCUUAUUUGUGUGAUACAAUAACCUUUAUGGUAGUUAUAAUUGGCAUUUUUAUUUGGUCUUGGCUUCUUGAGUAUAGGAACAUAUGCAUUGGAAUAUACCCAGAGGCACAUGAACGUGAUCAAUAUUUGUUGAAUGUAUGAACGAAUAUAAACUAAUGAAUCAAUCAUUAAACAUACUGCGGUUUAAAAUAGAAGUGUUGCCACCUUAAAUUUAUACCUUUUAGAGAUCAUACACUUAUAAAAUAUUUGGAAAUAUUUUUGGGAGUUACUCCUGGUUUGCCAAUAAGUAAAGAUAACUCAUUCCUUUAGAAGGGAAGAACUUUUUUUUUUUUCUGUUUCUGCCAUUCUUCCCUUUGCUCCUGCUCUACUUAGUUUAGUAUGCCCCUUCCUUCCAUACUCACCUGUUAAAAGAUAACCAAUCCACCCCACUCUCAUCCCCAGAGUGCUCGUGGGGAACUAAAACUUUAUUGCAUAAAUGCAGGAAGGAUUUGAGCAGGUGAAGUGGGACAAAGAGACUAGAAACUAAAAAAAAAAAAAAAAAAAAAAAAGAACUGACUAGCAUUAUAGCAGAGUGGCUCAGAGCAGAGGCUAUAGAAUGAAACAGAACUGAGUUUGAAUUCUUGUCCUGCCAUUCUUUUCUGAAUUCCCAUAAUUCUAACCUAACUUAGGUGGGUAUAAAGAAGGAUAAUAGUACCUAUUCCACUGAGUUGUCAUAUAUAUUAAAUGAGAUAAUUAGUGUAAAUAAAGUGCAUAGCACAUAAGCACACAUGGCAGCUUUAGUUGAAGGUGUUAUAUGUGUAAAUUCAUAAUGUGGAUCAAAGUGACUUAAUUUCCAUAAAUAUAUGUUUCUAAGUCUAAACAUUAGUCAAGGAUUGCAUUUUAUGUUCAUCAUCACAGAACUUACUGUUUAAAAAUAAAUGCUCACCAUAUGGAAUUACUGAGGGCAGAGUAUUGAAGUUCUUAAACAUAAGCAGGUGGAAGAUGGAGAAAGUUUGGAAUCACCUGGCUAAAGCCAUCCAAGAAACUGGAAGGUGCUUACUGUAGAACACUUCAUGCUCCCUCCCUCUCCAGGCCUUUGUAGGUGCUAUUCACUUUACCAGCAGUGCUCUUCUUGAGUUUCUUCACUUGCCUAAGUUCUACUCCUUUUGUUGCACUAGCUCAGAAGUUACCAUUUUCGGAAAUCUUUAUCUACUAGGACUAUGCAUUUAUCUGCAGAUAAUAGAAAAUCCUAACUAUAGAAUGAAACAACUGGUGGCUUAAAGUAGUAAGAAUUUGUGUCACCAAAUAAAGAGUCCAAAGUUAGGCAUUCAAGAGUAUUGCAAUAACUGCAAUGCCACCAGAGUCCUAGUCUCUUUUUUAUUUGCUAUGUUAUCUUUUGUUGUGUCACAUCACUGAUGGGCUGCUGUACCACUAUGCCUUUAGUCCAAAGACUAAGGCAGGAAAAAGGGAAGAAGGGCAAACGGGCUUUCUUCUAGGGAAGCCAUCUUUUUAUUCAGGACACCUCCUUAUAUUCAGGAAAACCACUUUAGGAACUUCAACCUCCAGAGUAAUGUCAACAUGGCUACCCCUACCUGCAAGUGGAACUAGGACAUCUUUUGUUUUCUAGUCUAAACCAGAGGAAGAAAAAGAAUGUGGUGGUUAGCAACAUAUGUGUCAUGAGACAACAUAUUAGUCAUGCUGUCCAGUGUUAAGGGCCCCAACUUUCUUGUACUCUGUGUAUAUCCCUAUCAAAGCUAUUACCAUGUACUAUGCUAUCGCCAGCUUAAUUUGUUUUCUUCUCCAGAAAUAAGUUUUGGAAGUAAGGGCUGGGACUUAUGUCUCUAUAUCCCUAGUACUUUAACACUGUCUUUUCAUGGAAGACACUCAGUAAAUAUUUACUGGAUCGUUAUUUACAAACAGUGAUUAUCAAAAAGUAAGUAAAUAUGCACAUAAUAUCCCCUAAACAAAGUUUCUUUGUUUUUUAUUGUUAUUGUUAGUAUUUAUUAAUUACUAUGAGGCAGACAAAGGCUUCACAUGUUUUAUCAUUCAGUCCUCAUAAUUUGCCUGUGAGGUUAAUGUGUCAUCAUUGUCAUUUUGCAGAUGAAGAAACAGACUCAGACAAGUUUAAGUAAUUUACCUAAGGUUUUAAAACUUACUUAUUGGUAGAGUUAGACAUUUAAUUCAGAUAAUCUGACUUCAGAUCCCAGACUUUUAAAAAACUAUGCUAUAUCAUGCUUUACAGAUUUUCUGAAGUAUGAGCUUAUAAUCAAGAAAAUGUUCCUUAUUUUUCCAAAUAGAAAGUAAUCUGAAAUGAAAAAUUAAAAACUGGACUCAUCUUACUGAAUUUUGGUAACCAAUAAUUGUAAACACAGUCUGUUUUUAUAAGCAGGUUGUCUGAAUGCCAUUUUAAAAACUUACAGUGUGCUCACUAAAGUGAAAUAGCUACAAUAAUGUUAGAUAUUUAAGUUGAUUCCAAUUAUGAAGACAAUAUGAAAUCUACUAGAAGUAAAAAAUAUAAAGUACUUUUCUAGUUUUAAAGCUAUGAAAAAAUUUAUCUGUUUAUUGGUAAAGACAAAUGAAAAUAUUUGUAGUAGCAUAAAUAUGAAUAGAUUUUUUUGUUAAUGUUUUAGUGCUUUUGCAGUGAAAAUGUAAUUUUUAACAAUAAGCAGCAUAUCUUAAACUAAAUUUCUUAUUUGAGUUGUAACAUUUUUAGAUGUAUAAUGUCAUAAUACACUUGUAAAGCUGAUCCAGUUACAUUUUUCAUAAUUAGUUUACUAGUGAGGGUAAUAUUUUACCCUUGAUAUAUCCAACACCAGAGCAUUAUUAGCUAAACCCAGCUGAGUGUAAGUUUCUCAGUCUAUAUUACCGAGUCCCCUUAUUUUACUUCAGUUACGUUGGUCUAUCGGAGAGGUAUAGUUAGGGACUAAAAUGUAAGAGAAAUAACUUUUUUUUUCCUUGAGACAUCGUCUCACUCUGUCACCCAGUUUGGAGUGCAGUGCCAUGAUCAUAGCUCACUGCAGCCUCAAAUUCCUGAGCUCAACUCAAGUGAUCCUUCUGCCUCAGCCUCCUGAGAAGCUGGGACUAUAGGUGCACACCACCAAACCCGGCAAAAAAAAUUUUGUUUUUUUGUAUGGAUGAGGUUUCAUUAUGUUGCCAAGGCUGGUCUUGAAUCAACUCCUGGCCUCAAGUGAUCCUCCUGCCUCAGCCUCCCAUGAGAAAGAAUUCUUAACAUGUGGUGUACAAAAGGCCUAGUCUGCUGAGAGUCAACCAAAGGAGGAUGGGAAAUAGUAAUCCAGUGUUUCCCAAAAUAUGCUCCUUGGAAUAGUAAUUCCAUAAAAUAGGAAUAUGUUAUGCAAAAGGUUCCGUAACCAGGCAUGGUAGCUGUCGCCCCAGCUACUCAGGCUGGGUGGAUUACUUGAGCUCAGGAGUUCCAGACUGCAGGAGCUACAAUUGUGCCGCCACAGUACAGUCUGGGUGACAGAGCAAGACCCCAUCUCUUUAAACCAAAAAAAAAAGUUCCAUAGUCAAGUAUGUUUAUGAAAUCAAUUAAAAGAUGUCUUAAAUGCUUUAUCAGCUGCUACAUGUCAUCAACCUUAUUUGUGCAGUAUGUUCCAAAAUUUUUUUGCUCUGAAUUCCUCUUCACCCUUUUCCUCAUACAACUUCUCAUGAAACUGGUGUUAUGAAACACAAUAUUUAUGAAAUAGUAAGGUCUAUAGGGCAAGUUUCUAGCAUAGAAAGAGAAAUUACUUUUUACAUAUUAUUCAUAAGUAACAGGAUGUUGAGAACUUCCUGUUUAUAUUACUGCCUUCAGGUGUGUAUACCAACAGGAAGCAGUCUCCCAACUAAUUCUAAUGUUUGGGUCCCCUAAAUUGACUAGUUUUGCUUUGGAGUUAUUAGAAAAAAUAAAGGUUAAGAGGGCUAUAUAUUUUGGUUCCCUUUAGCAAGGCUAAUGUAAAAUUAAAUAACAUUUAGCUUGCCAGGAAUUCAGCUGAAAACAAGAGAGAAGUAUUUCUAUCUCAUGGAUUCAGUAAUUCAACGCAAUCCUAGUAAGAUUUUAGAAGAGUAGACAACCUAGGCUGGUUGCCGUGGCUCAUGCCUGUAAUCCCAACACUUUCCGAGGCAGGAGAAUCCCUUGAGCCCAGGAAUUUGAGACUAGCCUGAGCAAUAUAGGGAGAUCCCAUCUCUACAAAAAAUAAAAAAUCAGCUGGGCAUGAUGGCAUGAACAUGUAUUCUCAGCUGCUUGGGAGGCUGAGGUGGGAAUAUCUCUUGAGCCCAGGAGGUCAAAGGCUGCAGUGAGCCAUGAACGUGCCACUGCACUCCAGCCUGGGUGACAGAAUGAGACCCUGUCCUAUCACCUGGCUGCAGAGAUCAAAGGCUUAAAACCAGGGAUAAAAGAGGCUGAGUAUUUUAAGUUCAUUUAAGUCUGUAUUACAUACCUUCCAGGAAGAGUGUACCAUCUUAUUUUCUAGGCUUUCUAACCAGCCAGUGUUCUAAGAAAGCAUUUUUAUGUUUUGCCAGCUAUUUCUAGGUUUAAAAAAUGCAGGUAGCCUAUAUUUUUGGUAACUUAGCAUACCCUAGUAAAGCAUCUGCUUUACAGGCCAUGCUAUGCUCAGCACCUGGAAGGCCAAGUAAACUCACCUGGUCAAAAAUGGAACGUGUCUAAUGAGUUCCUUCUCAUUGGUACGUAUAUGGCUUUCUGAAUUAAGUCAGCUCUACUAGGGUAGGGUUUAUUCAUGAGAACUGACCAAAGGAGGAUUUUCUAGGACUGUCAUUAGGAGAGAAAAUUUGAAAAAUGAUGUGGGGUUACCAGAAUACCUGUUGCUUCUGGAGGAUUAAGGGUAUUGUCACUUCCUGAAACUAGGUAACAGAUGCCAUCAUUUAGAUAAUUGUGUAGUGAGUCAGGUUCCUUCCAGGGGAGAAGUCUUAGUGAUGUCCUCUUGCAGGGGAAUAUAGUAAAAAACUUGUAGUUGGUAUAUUUUAAGUUUUAAACACUGAUUAUGUAAUCCUUUAAAACAGGGGUUCCCCAGGUAUGGUUCAUGGCCUGUCAGGAACCGGGCCACACAGCAGUAAGUGAGCAGCAGGCGAGCAAGCAUUACUGCCUGAGCUCCGCCUCCUGUCAGAUCAGCAGCGGCAUUAGAUUCUUAUAGGAGCACAAACCCUAUUGUGACCUGAGCAUGUGAGGGAUCUAGGUUAUACGUGCCUUAUGAAAAUCUAACUAAUGCCUAAUGGUCUAAGUGGAACAGUUACGUCCCAAAACCAUCCCCAUAAUCCCCACCCCAUCCAUGGAAAAAUUGUCUUCUGUGAAACUGGUCCCUGGUACUGAAAAGCUUGGGGACCAUUGCUUUAAAAGACUUUUUCUUUCUACCUUCCAACUCUACUGGCACAGUGUUUGUACUCCUGAGGCAAAUGAUCAAAAUUAACAGCCUAAGCUGUGUUCUCUAAAAACUGUCCUACUUUAGUGAACAGCAAAGCCUAUUAUGAGAUAAACCUUAAGAACCAACUUUCUGGGCACACAUGAGUUGUCCAUUACAAAAAUCUAAAACCUAAAAAAGAAAAAAAAUCGCGGCAGAGGUACUAACUACCCCAUGUGAAAAAUCCAAUUUUAGCAUAGUUAAAAUCAGGCAAAGGAAGGCAGUGCAAGCAGUCUGUUGGUAGGAAGUCUGUUCAUGUAUCAUGGUUAUCUGUGUGGAAUUUCAGUAGUACCUGAGUUCUCACCAGGAUCCUAUCUGGGACACUGCAAUAGAUAUUAUUUCCCUGGGUAUAACCUUCCUAGUCUCAUCUCCAUCUUGGCUUAAUGGAAUCUUAUUGGUAUGGCUUGCUCCAUAUCUAAGUGCUGUAUGUUUCACAGAUCUUGGAUAUUAAAACAUAUGAUUGCUCAGAUAUAGUCUGGAUGGUAAUAACAAACAGGUGUGGUCCAGCAAAUCAAGCAUCUGGUGCUUAUGGCCCUGGAAGGAAUCAGCUACUGACCCUGUAGAUGGACCAGAAGGGCUAAACUUGAGACCCACAGCUAGAUCUCUUCCACAAAAUUGUUUUGUUUGGCCCACACUGAUGUUCUAAAAUUUUUGGAUUGGUUGCCAUAUUUUAGAAAGAGGAAAGUUCACAGAAAAACUUAGGUAUUUGUUUUCUCUUUUCUCUUGAAAACAGGACACUGAACCCUUGUUUGCGCAUGACAGCAGUUGAACCUAAGUAGUGGUUAUUCCUUUUAAACAUGACAUGCACUCUUUAAUCCUCUUAGUCCCCACCAUGCUUUUACCUCAUCAGAUUUUUCUUACCUAUGUUCUACUGUACUCAUGUGCAUUACGUGCCUGGCGUUUGAGUUUGUGGCUUUUGUGUUAGAUUAUUUGGGGGCAAGGUUAUUAUAAGAGCUAUUCUUUACAGGGUUGGGGACCCAUAAUGGUACAUAUGAGGAUAGAUAAUGGGAAGAAAGCCUCUGUUUUUAUUUCUUAGUAAUAUGGAGUCUUUACUGUCAGUUCCUGCUUUAGCUGCCAUUACAACGGCCAGCCAAUAGAAAGCAAAAAUAGUAUAUAACAAAGAAUAAUGAUAACUGUUUUGAGUCUCUGCUAUAGAUCAGCCACUGUGUAAAACAUGUUGCCUUCUCACUUUCCUGUGAGACCAUCCUUGAUUACUCUAUUUUAAAUUGUGGUUUAACAUACCCUCCCAACACUUUUUCUUCAUAGCGUUUAUCAUCAUCAUGUAACAUAUGUUUUACUUUUAAAUUUUAUUGUAUGUCUUCCUGUUACUAAAAUAUAAGAUAGUGCCUAGAGCAUAGUAGGCACUUGAUGCUAGAUGAAUAUAUAAAUGAAUAAUGUUGUUUAAUUUUUAAACUUUCCAAGUCUGUCCCAUGGUUUAGUGUUUUAAAUCAGAAGCCAGUCUUCUUCAUUUACUUACUGCUAAAGUGUUCCUGAGAAACAGACCUACUAUUAGAAUGGGGCCUUCUAAGAGGUGACACACUCCCAGCAAUAAAUUUGAGUAGUUCACUCCAGUAGUAAUUCUUAACAAUUACUUUCCUGCCCUCCAGAGAUAUAUGCUGCAUCUGUGAGGGGUUAUGGAUGUGUGGAGUAUGCAAUUCCAAAAAAUUAUCUUCUUCCCUUUACAAGAGAAAGCAUGCUUUCUCACCUCAAAUCCUUGCUUUAAUGAAUACUAAAUGGUGACCAAGGUCAACUCACCGACACAGACUUGAUUGAAACUAAAAUUUUGUUUGCAUUAUCUAAUUAAAAUAUAUCAAAUAAAUAAAUAACAAAAAUUCACCUGUUACUGCUCGAAAAAGGCUCAUGGGUAGAAGAUCACAUUUAUUUUGUGAUACGGCACUGGAGUUACUGUUAGUAAGAUUUAUCUCAGAAUCUUAUUUUUUCUUUCUAUUCACUUAGUGGAGAAGAAAUAGGCACUUUUCAAAAUGAAGAGCAUGUCUGUGCAGAAUUUACUUGAAUGAGAAAACUUGGCAGUGGGGCCAGAUUUAAAUAGCUUGUUUGGUUUUGUUUAGUAUCACAAAAAGAAAUAAUUUAUAUAAGGCCAUGCCAUUUAAAGGAUUGUGAACCUUUUACUCUUUCCUUUUUUUACAUUAAACACUUGAGUUAUUGUAUCCUCCUUUAGUAUGUGAGAAAAACAUGGUUAUUAAUGUUUUUUUUUUCUCUCCUGUUAGGGACUCGAGUGGACUAAAUUGCCACUGAGCCCCAAAAAAAUAAGUUCUGGUAACUUUUGUGUUUCAUGAUUAUAAACAAUGCUCUAACCAUUGUCAGCUAGCUUUCAAAUUUAUUACAUUGUCUCAAAAAUAUGAUGGGAAUUUCUCAUCAUUACCAGAAAGAAAUGCAAUUUUCAUUAAUAUGUUUAUAUUCAAAGAAUGACAUAAUACACAAAAGUGUGCUCUGAUGGAAACAAAUGAAUUCUUACAGUAUUCUAAUUUUUCUAUCUUUGCACUUUAAGUCAUUUCAAACUUGCAGAAAAGUAAACUCUAGGGGAGAAAAGAAGGAAAGGUUACUAGGAACAGAGAAAACAGAGACUAAAGAAUUGACUUUUCCUCUCAAUGGCCUACCUGUUUGUUAAGGCUGUAACUUUGUAAUCUUGAAGAAUCCAGUAGAAAUCCAGUUUUUUGAAAGCAUUGUGGCAGCUGGACUGUCAAGUACCAUCAUUUUUUUACAUGCUGAAAAAAGUUAAAAACACAGUGACUAGAAAGAUCUAAACCUUAUCCUUCUUGCUGAUACCACCACCCAUCCCCACCUGCUAGUAGAACUGUGUGAUCUUUUCAAAUAGCACACAGAAACAUUGAUAAUAACCUUGGCUUCUCCUGAGUGAUUCAGAGUGAAUUUAGGGGAAUGUUACAUGAUGAUCCUAUGAUGGUCAGUUUUUGUAGAAUUUAACAAUGGGAAGAUGUGUUCUUAAGAUGGCUCUCAUUUGAAUUCUAUUUCAAGGGGACUGAAAUAUUUUGGCUUUGGUACCCUUUGGCUAUUUGAACCAUAGUUCCUACUAUAUGAGUGUUUUAGCAGUAUGCCCUUGUCUAAGCAUUUCAUUUGGUUCUUACUUUGGCACUUAUGAAGCCAAAGAUACUAUGAUACUACGGUACUUUCUACCGUGUUAUUCAUUAUCUCAGUUUCAGAGAUUCAGCUUCCUUUUUUACUAUUAAGUUCUAAAAAAUUCAUUGUAGUUGUGUUUCUUUCCGGAUUUAUCUUUUGAUUUAUCAUCAAUUUAUGAACUCAGUUUCUUUAAAGUAUUAAACAGGCAAAUAUAAAUAGCUAAGAAAACCGAAAUAUAUUUUAGAGCACAUUCAUAAAAAUUACCAAUGAAUGUCCCUACUUUUUUCUUUUAUAAUGUAAUAUAAUCAUUUCUUAGUUUUAUGUGCAGAAACUUCUCAAUAUUAAGCACAGAAUCUACUUAGUAAUAUCUUACAUGUCUAUCUUGGAGUAAGAAUUUGUCAGUGCUAAUGUUGCAGCCCCUUGGGGCUUCUUAAUAUUGGAAUUUCUCCAGGCUUGAUUAUAGUUGAGGGAAGUUCAAAGGGAAUUUUUUUAUUGUUUAGCUUGUUUUUAGGUUGCAGUAAAUUCUCUAGGUCAUCCAGCAGGAUUAGGAAGAGAAGCAUUGUGAGAAACAGGUUUUGGGUUUUGCUGAAAUUUGCUUGUCAGCAUUGCAUCACUUUUCCUUAACUGUUCUCUAAGUACUGAUGUCUUUCAAAUUGACUCAGAUCAUACUCCUUAUCUUUGAGCAGAAUAUUUUGAACAGAAAAUUAAGCCAUUUUCAUUUAUAUACCUAAUUCAAUAGGUUUAUAAAUAAAAGGGCAAAUCCUCACGAUAAUACAGUACAGUAAAAAUUGCUCUCCCCCUAGAACUGAGAAUAGAAAAACAAUUUCCUCUUACAUUGUUUAUAGUAGGUAGCCCUUAAAAGAAAAUCACUUAUCCCUGCCACCCCCAGUGGUCCUCAUAACAAGUUAGGAAACUGAAAAUUGCUGAAAAUUAAGAAUUCUAAGCAACAAGCAUGGAAAAUAGAGUCCUCAUACCUGACCUUUUUCUCUAUCUUCCUUACUCAAUCCUGUGGAAGAACUGCUGGGGCCUGAGAGAAUAUAAUAUCAGCAAGAAGUUGAGAAGUUUACAGACCUAGAGAAACUCUACCUCUACCUUCAGCUGCCUUCUGGUCUCAGCAAUGGAGAGAAAAGUGAUCAGAAUGCCAUGUCAUCUAGUCGGGCACAACAAAUGCAUGCCUUUUCCUGGAUUCGGAAUACCCUAGAGGAACAUCCGGAGACUUCACUGCCCAAACAGGAAGUCUAUGAUGAGUACAAGAGCUAUUGUGACAAUCUUGGUUACCAUCCAUUAAGUGCUGCUGAUUUUGGAAAGAUCAUGAAAAACGUCUUUCCAAACAUGAAGGCACGUCGUUUGGGCACAAGAGGCAAAUCUAAAUAUUGCUACAGUGGACUAAGAAAAAAAGCUUUUGUUCAUAUGCCAACACUGCCCAACCUUGACUUUCACAAAACUGGAGAUGGGUUGGAAGGAGCUGAACCUUCUGGGCAGCUUCAAAAUAUUGAUGAAGAAGUUAUCUCUUCUGCUUGCCGUCUUGUGUGUGAGUGGGCCCAGAAAGUGUUAAGCCAACCAUUUGACACCGUCUUGGAAUUAGCCCGCUUCCUUGUAAAAAGUCACUAUAUAGGCACCAAGUCAAUGGCAGCUCUAACUGUAAUGGCAGCAGCACCAGCAGGAAUGAAAGGAAUUACCCAGCCUUCUGCUUUUAUACCUACAGCUGAAAGUAAUUCCUUUCAGCCUCAGGUGAAGACUUUGCCAUCUCCAAUUGAUGCUAAACAGCAGUUGCAACGGAAAAUCCAGAAGAAGCAGCAAGAACAGAAACUACAAUCCCCUUUGCCAGGAGAAUCUGCAGCAAAAAAGUCAGAAAGUGCUACAAGCAAUGGAGUGACUAAUCUUCCUAAUGGAAAUCCUUCAAUCCUUUCUCCUCAACCUAUUGGUAUCGUUGUGGCAGCUGUCCCUAGUCCCAUUCCGGUCCAGCGGACUAGGCAAUUGGUAACUUCACCGAGUCCAAUGAGUUCUUCUGACGGCAAAGUUCUUCCCCUCAAUGUACAGGUGGUCACUCAGCACAUGCAGUCUGUGAAACAGGCACCAAAGACUCCCCAGAACGUUCCAGCCAGUCCUGGUGGGGAUCGUUCUGCCCGGCACCGUUACCCUCAGAUCUUACCCAAACCAGCGAACACCAGUGCACUCACCAUUCGCUCUCCAACUACUGUCCUCUUUACUAGUAGUCCCAUCAAAACUGCUGUUGUACCCGCUUCACACAUGAGUUCUCUAAAUGUGGUGAAAAUGACAACAAUAUCCCUCACACCCAGCAACAGUAACACCCCUCUUAAACAUUCUGCCUCAGUCAGCAGUGCUACAGGAACAACAGAAGAAUCAAGGAGUGUUCCACAGAUCAAGAAUGGUUCUGUCGUGUCGCUUCAGUCUCCUGGGUCCAGGAGCAGCAGUGCGGGGGGAACAUCUGCUGUGGAAGUCAAAGUGGAACCCGAAACAUCAUCAGAUGAGCAUCCUGUACAGUGCCAAGAGAACUCUGAUGAGGCUAAAGCUCCCCAGACACCUAGUGCCCUUUUGGGGCAGAAAAGUAAUACAGACGGAGCACUGCAGAAACCUUCAAAUGAAGGUGUCAUUGAAAUAAAAGCAACUAAGGUCUGUGACCAGAGGACCAAAUGUAAAAGUCGCUGUAAUGAAAUGCUGCCAGGCACGUCAACAGGCAAUAAUCAAAGCACUAUCACUCUAUCAGUUGCUUCUCAGAACUUAACUUUCACCAGCAGCAGCUCACCACCUAAUGGUGACUCAAUCAAUAAAGACCCUAAAUUAUGCACUAAAAGCCCAAGAAAACGACUGUCUUCUACAUUGCAGGAGACCCAGGUGCCUCCUGUAAAGAAACCAAUUGUGGAACAGCUUUCAGCAGCUACCAUAGAAGGGCAGAAACAAGGCAGUGUUAAGAAGGACCAAAAGGUUCCACAUUCAGGGAAAACAGAAGGUUCAACAGCAGGUGCUCAGAUUCCUAGCAAGGUAUCAGUAAAUGUCAGUUCACACAUAGGAGCAAAUCAACCCUUGAAUUCCUCUGCCCUUGUUAUCAGUGAUUCAGCUUUGGAACAGCAAACAACCCCAUCAUCAUCUCCAGAUAUAAAAGUAAAACUUGAAGGAAGUGUCUUUCUCUUGGACAGUGAUUCAAAGUCAGUUGGCAGCUUUAAUCCAAAUGGAUGGCAACAAAUCACUAAAGAUUCUGAGUUUAUAUCUGCCAGUUGUGAACAACAGCAAGAUAUCAGUGUUAUGACAAUUCCUGAGCACUCUGAUAUCAAUGACUUAGAGAAAUCUGUUUGGGAAUUAGAAGGAAUGCCACAGGACACAUAUAGCCAGCAGCUACAUAGCCAGAUACAGGAAUCUUCUUUAAAUCAAAUACAAGCACAUUCUUCAGAUCAGUUACCUCUGCAAUCUGAACUGAAGGAGUUUGAGCCUUCUGUUUCCCAGACAAAUGAAAGCUACUUUCCUUUUGAUGAUGAACUUACACAAGAUAGUAUUGUGGAAGAGCUGGUGCUUAUGGAGCAGCAAAUGUCAAUGAACAAUUCUCAUUCUUACGGCAACUGUUUGGGAAUGACCCUUCAGAGUCAGUCAGUAACUCCAGGAGCUCCAAUGUCAUCUCACACUUCCAGCACCCACUUCUAUCAUCCAAUCCACAGCAAUGGCACUCCAAUCCACACACCCACACCCACACCCACACCCACUCCUACUCCAACCCCAACCCCAACCCCGACAUCUGAAAUGAUUGCUGGAUCUCAGAGUCUGUCACGGGAGAGCCCUUGCUCCAGGCUAGCCCAGACUACACCUGUGGAUAGUGCUUUAGGAAGUAGCCGACAUACACCCAUUGGUACUCCACAUUCUAACUGCAGCAGUAGUGUCCCCCCCAGCCCUGUUGAAUGCAGGAAUCCGUUUGCAUUCACUCCAAUAAGCUCCAGUAUGGCAUAUCAUGACGCCAGCAUUGUCUCAAGUAGUCCUGUGAAACCGAUGCAAAGACCCAUGGCCACACACCCUGACAAAACCAAGCUUGAAUGGAUGAAUAAUGGGUAUAGUGGGGUUGGUAAUUCAUCAGUUUCUGGCCAUGGUAUUCUCCCAAGCUAUCAGGAACUAGUGGAAGACCGUUUCAGGAAACCUCAUGCUUUUGCUGUGCCUGGACAGUCUUAUCAGUCUCAAUCCAGACAUCAUGACACUCAUUUUGGUCGUUUGACUCCUGUCUCUCCUGUGCAGCAUCAAGGUGCCACUGUAAAUAACACCAACAAACAGGAGGGUUUUGCAGUCCCUGCCCCUCUUGAUAAUAAAGGAACUAAUUCAUCUGCCAGCAGCAACUUCAGAUGCCGGAGUGUGAGCCCUGCUGUUCAUCGCCAACGUAAUCUUAGUGGAAGCACCCUCUAUCCAGUAUCUAAUAUCCCACGAUCUAAUGUGACCCCCUUUGGAAGUCCAGUUACCCCAGAAGUUCAUGUUUUCACAAAUGUUCACACAGACGCAUGUGCCAACAACAUAGCUCAAAGAAGCCAAUCAGUUCCAUUGACAGUCAUGAUGCAGACAGCCUUCCCAAACGCUCUUCAGAAGCAAGCAAACAGUAAAAAAAUAACCAAUGUUUUGUUGAGUAAACUUGAUUCCGACAAUGAUGAUGCAGUGAGAGGUUUGGGAAUGAACAACCUGCCCUCUAAUUAUACAGCCCGGAUGAAUCUCACUCAGAUUUUGGAACCUUCCACUGUUUUUCCUAGUGCCAACCCACAAAAUAUGAUCGAUUCCAGCACUUCUGUUUAUGAGUUCCAAACACCAUCUUACCUCACCAAAAGUAAUAGCACCGGUCAGAUCAAUUUUUCUCCUGGAGAUAAUCAAGCACAAUCAGAAAUUGGAGAGCAACAAUUAGAUUUCAAUAGCACUGUUAAAGACCUGUUGAGUGGAGACAGCUUGCAAACCAACCAGCAGCUGGUAGGUCAGGGAGCAUCUGAUCUCACUAAUACUGCAUCUGAUUUCUCUAGCGAUAUCAGGUUGUCUUCUGAGCUCUCAGGCAGCAUCAAUGAUUUGAACACUUUAGACCCAAAUCUACUGUUUGAUCCAGGUCGUCAGCAGGGACAAGAUGAUGAAGCUACACUGGAAGAAUUAAAGAAUGACCCAUUAUUUCAACAAAUUUGCAGUGAAUCCAUGAAUUCUAUGACUUCAUCAGGUUUUGAAUGGAUAGAAAGCAAGGACCAUCCUACUGUUGAAAUGUUGGGUUAAAUUGUGUUUUAUAACAUGUAGCACACUGUAUCUAAAGACAUAUGUAUUGUAUUUGUCUUAAUGGAAGUGCCUCCCGCAGCAGAAAUACUAUUAAUUGUGACAUUUUAAAAGCGUUUGCUGCAGAAGUGGUUUCUUCAGUAGGAAAUGGUUAGACUUGCCUCAGUUCUUAACAAGUGUCUAAAGACAGUAGGCUGUAGAAGAACAAGUAUUAGGUUUUAAAUUUUAUAAUGUGCCCCAUUUAUUCACAUUGAUUGACUAUCCAGCUGUUACAAGAGCAGUCGAUCUUUAUUUUGUGUAAGUUAGUUUCAUUUCAUCAGAUGAUCUGCACAGAACUCAGAAUAAACCAUCAAUUUUAGGUAUAGGCUGUUUUGUUGUUGGCAUUAUCUUUUAGAUAUAAAAUCAUAGCUAGGGUGAACUGUAGACAAGAAAGUCUUCCUUGAAACAGGGAUAAUAUUCAGGUUAUUAUAAAUAUUUAGGCUUGAAGCAUAGAGCUACUGUAGGGUGAAAAAUCUCUGUAGGACUUUCUGGGGCUUCAGUACCAUUUACACCCACGAUGAAGGGCUUAAAUAGAAAAUAAUGGAAAAUUAAAUAUUACUUUAAGGAAAGCAAAGCUGCACUAAAAUUUUUAAGGGAAAAAAAACAAGUAGCCAUUUAUAUUUGUGACCUUGCAUUAAUAUUUAAAUGUUGAUUUUAAUAUGGAGCUAGCACACAUAGAUGCGCAGGCACGCACACACAAAACAAGCAAAUGUAACUCCAGGCAUUUGUAAUUUAAUAUAAUAAAUACAAGCAUGUUAGAAAAAUGCUUUAUGUCUUAUUAUUUGUUAAGUUAGGGGAAUGAGAAGGAAAACAAAAGCAUUCUCUUAGUUUCAUCACAAUGGCUGCAUGUACAUAUUGAGAUUCUAACUGAGAUUUACUUUGAAAUUUUUCAUUAAAAUAUUCCACAAUAAUCAGUUUUUUUCCUCUUCAAUUGAGUGACUGACUCCCUCACUCCUCCUGAAUAUAGUAAUGUAGUUUGAUCAUAGGAUCCCUUUGAAAAACAGGAAGGAGGAUAACAUAAAAAACAACAAAAAACAUUUCACCACCUAAGGUCUGAAGCCACAAAUCUUUAUAUCUCUGAUGAAACAAAGGGGAUAUCAAUAGUACUUGAAGAAGAAGAGCAUUUUAUUACUUGCUUAAUUUAUUUAUUGUGAUAACCACAAUUGCAAAAGAAGAACUCAGGAUUUGUUUUAAAAUGUUUCUCUCUAUGGCUCCCAUUUUGUUUUGUGAAUAAUUAUUUAUGAGUUGCAUGUUGACACAAACCUACUCACUGGUUGAAAGCUCCAUUUAAGUGAGUUUCAAGAUCACUUUCAAAGAGAUUUUUAAAUUGCCAUUGUUUUUAAAGCUAACAUAAAACCAUUUGCUAUGCUACCUUGAACCUAGCUAAGCUUUCCUUUACCUUAGUAAGCCAAUCAGAAGACUACAAUCAAUGAAUAUUUAGCAAAUGUGCUGAAGGGUUUAAUAAGGUUUUGUUGUUCAAUAAAUUUGCAAGGUAGGGUAUUAACAUAUUUUGAUAAAUAAAUGGUGCUAGAGUUGGCGCAGAGGUUUAUAUAUUGAUAUGUCUUAGUUAUUGGCAUUUGUGUGUGUUUGCUGUUAUCUUGAUUUCAUGAUUUGUUAGGUAUUUUUUUCUUGAUGCUAGUUAUUUCUUCACUGUACAUUGAGACACAGCACUACUGCACACCAAAGUAUGCAAUACCCAAAGGAAACUGUGUGAUUUCUCCUGACAAAUGAUGGGAGCCUUUCUUUAUGAGAUACUCUGAAAAGGAGAUUUUGAGGCCAUUCUAAUCCCUUGUUUACAUUAUUAGCUUCCUACUAAUAUAAAAAUAAUGGAAAUCUUUUUUGAUAAAAAUAUUAAGACUGGAGGAUUUUUAACCCCUUGUACAGUAUUGCAGCAAACUCUUUAAAUUUGGUUGAAUUCGUCCAGCAAACUUUCUGGGGUUCAUAUAUUGCACUAAAUUUGUUGAACCUGUGGUAGGCACAUCUCUUAGGAUAAAUGCAACCAAUACAGUCCACAGAUUAAACUUUUUAAAUGUGUUUCAUUAUGAAAAGACAAAAUGUCAUCAAAGUGACAGAUAAAAUUGUCUUAUGUAGCAAUGUGCAUUGAUCUCAAUGAGAUAUUUCUAUUAUUCUCUUACAUGAGAAUAUUACAGCAGGAAGAAUUAAGUUUAGUUUGCUUCACCAUGUUAAUACAUGAUCACAAAAUGUGCAUGAGUGUUAUUGACUUAUCUUGUACAGUACUAGGAUUCCUGUAACCACUCUUUUUUUUCUUCGCUGUAUUGAAACUGGUUCAGUGUUAACCAGGCAAGCAUAGUUAUUCACAGGUUAUUUACUUUAUGUUUACUAAUUCUGCUUAGUUAUUGUUGAAUAUGUUCUGUUCCAGAUUAUUUUUAUUGUUUUGAUGUUUAAAACAUUUUGCAUACUGUUUAUCAUAAAACUUCAUGAAGUAAAUAAUUUUGCAUAUAAUUGCAAUAAGCACUGACUUUUGAACUGAAAAGAAGGAAAGUGUUUUUUUGUGCAGUGCUUCUGAGGUUCAUAUAAUAGUCUUGUACUAUAAUGUGCUUUACUACACGAUAAAUGACAAAAACAAGCCCUGUUUCAUGUUUCAUUUAGUGCAAAAAGUCAGAUUUCCCCAGUGUUUUGUUGUCUGUUGUACCUGCUGAAACUACAGUAGUUGAAUAUUGCGGUAGCAUUUCAGUUCUCUUUUUUUAUUAAAGUGCUCAAAAAUUGUUUUUUAAAUGUUUUCAAAAACAAUUAAAAACAUUUUAUAUUAAACUGACUGGAUCUGAAGGUGUUUUAUGGGACAUAUUUUAUAUAGGCAACACAUUUUGUAAACAGACCCAAUGUUAUUCUUCCUUUGAUGUCAUUAACUUUAGGGAGUGAAUAAAAAUGAGCAGAAGGCAGAACAGUGCUGCUGAUCUGCUGUGUGCUAUUAAUCCAGAAGAAUACACAGAUCUUAGUUCAUUCAUCAAAACUCUGUUGUUCACUUAAGAUUAUUACCAAUGAAUGGUGCAUGGCAUAGAACUUUAUGUUGUCCAAAAAGCCAUCUUUUUCUCUUUCACAUAGUGUUUAAAUGUUAGCCUAUGGAGUACCUAGGUAAGUAUAUUUCUGGAGCUCUGAAUAGAAAAUGAGAAAAUUUUAAGCAUAGCUGUGUUCAAAAGCAGUAUAGACAUUUCCAGGUACCAGAAAUAACAAACUGAUAAGUGUAAUGAAUUUGUAAGCCAGAAGCUGGGCUACAGGUCUGGAAGCAGGCCGAAGUAGCCAGAAAUGUCAGCUCCUGCAAAGUAAUGAAACCAGGGUCUUGAAUGGAGUUUCCUCACUCUUGAAACUGAGAAGCAACAACAACCAGUGCCAGGGACUAUAUAUUGUAGACAGAUCUUCUCAAACAGCCUACUCCUCUGUUUACAUAGAUCUUUGUAGAUCUGUGAUAGUUCCACUAUCACCAUAGAUCUGGAGCCCUCAGUUUGAACAGGUGGUAGAAGCAAUUACAAAAGGAAAGGAGUGGAGAUUAGGAAGGGAGAGGUAAAGAGCAGGAAGGCUCCCAUGAAAGCUGAGCCUGCAGAUCAAAAUUCAAAAGUACUUGAAGAAAAACUAAUCCCAAGAAAGGCAAUCAGUCACUCAAGAGAAAAUGAAAGUAAUGAACUACCUAGAUAAUACUAUAAAAUUAGUAUGUUAGGAUCCUCAGUGCUCAAUGACAUGGAAGGGUAAAAUGUCAGAGCAGGCAAACAUAAGAACCAGUGCAUAGAGUCAACCAGUAAGAAAUUCUGGGGGUGAAAAUACUGUGUAACACCUGAGGUGAUUUUGGUUUCAAGUAAUUGAAAACCCAACACUGGCUUAAACCAUAAGGACACUUACUUUUAGCUUAAUAAUAGUGGAGAUAGGAGGUUCAAGGGUUCAUUCAAUGGUUCAUUGUUUACAGGCACCAGAUCCUGUUUGUGUUUCUGUUCCAUCAUCUUCAGCUUUGCUUUGCUGUGUCUAUUACCUCAUAGUCACAAGAUGGCUGCCACAGCUCAGAUGUUAUACCCUCAUAACAUCCCAAGCAGGAUAGUAAGAGCAGUUCUUAGCCUUUUAUCAGAGAGAAAAAAAAAUCUCAGAAUCUUCCAUUAAGCACUCCAUACACACACACUGUUAGUCUCAUUGUAUUAAACAAAGGCUCAUCCUAAGGCCAAUUACUUAGCUUAGAUCCUUAAUUAAUGCUUUAUAGGUAGGAGGGGGGGCCCAUUUCCUGGAGCAUGUGGUCAUUCAUCUUAAAUGAGUUCCAUCACCUAGGGAAGAUAUUAGGGACUUGCUCUUUGGGAGGCAACCAGUAGUGGUCACUGCAAAAAAUAGCUAGGUAAGAUGAGUAAGAUCUUGUACCCACCUUUGAGGGGCUUACAAUCAUAAAGAGUUAAGUACAUGUUCUUUGUUAAGUGCCAACAGUAUGUAUACUACACUAUGUAGAAGAAAAAAUAAGAAUUUGAAAUCUGCCGAACUAAGUUUACUGGUGCUAACUGUUAACUGGUAUCUUGCCUUCCCCCUAUGAGCUGAAAAAUCAGGUAUUAUUGAGUAUCACAAAUGCAAGUUGCCUCAGCUCCUACAGCAUAAGAAAAGACCAAACUUUUUAUUUUGUUAAAUCUGAAGUACAGAUUUAUUUUGACAUGCAUUGUUAUAAAUGAAUUUUUAAAUAAUUAAAGUUAUAAAUUUAUGGAUGGGAUCACUUAUUAAUAUUGCAUCAUCUGAAAUUUUAAAAAUAUGUAUGCCAGUCUUGUUGCUAUAAUCUGCUUAGAAAAAAGAACAAAACAAAAAGACUACAUUUUUCAAGAUUUGAUUUUUAAGAAGUACUUAAUUCUUGGAGAGGAGAAGAGAGUCAUAUAAAUAAAAUAUAUCAUGAGAGUGAUAUUACUGUGGUAUAUAGAGUAUUUCUUUGCAUUAGACCCAGUGUUAGUUUGCAUAUAUUCUCAUGUCCUCAUUGUAACAAUUUUUAGCGAGUAUUAUUUUUCAGGUGAGAAAAUUUUACUUCAGAGAUUAACUGGUGGAGGUAACAUAAUAACAGGAAGAGCCAGGAUUAUCUUAAUUUCAAAUCCCACUUCAUACCAUUAUGCUAUACUUAAGAUAUGUGUUCACAGUGUACCUACUGCAGUUGUAUGAUCUGGUUGCUUCUUUGAAAUUUUCAUUCUGGUUUUAAAUUUAGAAUUGAGUUUGAUUUUUGUGGAGUUCUUUAUUUAACCUCCCAUCCUUAUAUGUCAACAAUUCUUUUUCAUUUUUAUUGCUUUUAGAUUUACCUGUAGUUUGUAAUUUUCCUCCAAAUUACUUGAAUCCUUUUCCCUCCCUUCUCUCCAUAGAAAUACCCUGAUGUAUUAGGAGAAUGAAGAUUUAAAAACAAAAUUUUGUUUUCCACACAGCUUUUCAAGCAUAUUUCAUACAGGUAUACUCUAGUCAUAUUUAUGUUUAAAUCACUUAAAAUGUCAUCAAAAUAAAAAUGGGACUUUUUUUUUAACAGAUGAUAAAGUGCCUAAAAUAUGUCAGUCUCUGUACAAGGUGCUAGAGAAGACACCUGCCAUUUUGAAAUUUUGCAAUAUAAUGAAAAAGACACAGUGAAUGUCUUUGCAGGAUGCAAUGAGGUCACUAUAGCAGAGGCGGAUACUUACCAGUAGUAUGCAUUCUCCCCUUCUUCUUUACUGUAAAAGUCCUUGAUUUUUAGCUGAGCACACAGCCAUCUGACCAAAAGGCUGCAUCUGCCAACUUCCCUUGCAGUUAAGUGGAGACACUUACCAAGUACUCAAAGAGAUGUAACCAAAAGGUUUGGGUGCUACUUCUUUGCAGUGUUCUUGUCCUUCCUCUCUGCUGGCUGGAAUGCAAAUGUGAUGGCUAGAACUCAAGCAGCCCUCCUGGACUUCAUGUUAAAGACACAUGCUGAGGAUGAUUGAGCAACAAGAUACAAGGAGCCCAGGGCAUGAUGACUUUGGAAGGGAAGAUGCCCAACUAGUCCUGACUGCUUACCUCUGGAUGUGUUUUACAUGAGAGAAAUAAAUGUCUUUCUGGUUUAACUCACA